GGCUCGGACCGUAGCUAGGCGCUGGGCGGCCACCGGCUGGCCAGGCAGGCCUGCCAGGAUGGAGGGGCAUGCUGGGAUGGAGGGGCAUGCUGAAAUGGAGAUGCUGAGGACACUGAAGGGGCCUUCCACAGGGGAGGUCAGCAUGCACUUGGUGGCCGGAGACAGCCCCGGUUCUGGUCCUCACCUGCCCGCAACUGCCUUCAUCAUUCCAGCCAGUUCGGCCACCCUCGGCCUGCCCAGCAGUGCCCUGGAUGUGUCUUGCUUUCCCCGGGAGCCAAUCCAUGUGGGUGCCCCGGAGCAAGUGGCCGGCUGCGAACCAGUUUCUGCCACCGUCCUGCCGCAGCUUAGCGCCGGGCCGGCCAGCUCCAGCACCAGCACAGUGCGGCUUCUGGAAUGGACAGAGGCCGCGGCCCCGCCCCCAGGGGGCGGCCUGCGGUUCCGGAUAAGCGAGUAUAAGCCGCUGAACAUGGCGGGAGUGGAGCAGCCCCCGAGCCCCGAGCUGCGGCAGGAAGGCGUGACCGAAUACGAAGAUGGCGGGGCCCCGGCGGGAGAUGGCGAGGCGGGCCCCCAACAGGCGGAGGACCACCCCCAGAAUCCUCCAGAAGAUCCCAAUCAGGACCCCCCAGAGGAUGAUAGCACCUGUCAGUGCCAGGCGUGCGGGCCUCACCAAGCCGCGGGUCCAGAUCUUGGUUCCUCUAAUGAUGGCUGCCCUCAGCUGUUCCAGGAGCGGUCAGUCAUAGUGGAGAACUCCUCAGGCUCUACCAGCGCUUCUGAGCUCCUCAAACCCAUGAAGAAGAGGAAGCGCAGGGAAUACCAGAGCCCAUCAGAGGAGGAGUCGGAGCCAGAGGCCAUGGAGAAGCAAGAAGAAGGAAAGGACCCAGAGGGACAACCCACUGCUAGCACCCCAGAGAGUGAGGAGUGGAGCAGCAGCCAGCCUGCAACAGGUGAGAAGAAGGAAUGCUGGUCGUGGGAGUCCUACCUAGAGGAGCAGAAGGCCAUUACUGCUCCAGUCAGCCUCUUCCAGGACUCCCAGGCAGUCACUCACAACAAGAAUGGCUUCAAACUGGGCAUGAAGUUGGAAGGCAUUGACCCUCAACACCCGUCCAUGUACUUCAUCCUCACCGUGGCUGAGGUAUGUGGCUAUCGCCUACGCCUGCACUUUGAUGGGUAUUCUGAGUGCCAUGACUUCUGGGUCAAUGCCAACUCCCCUGACAUUCACCCUGCUGGCUGGUUCGAGAAGACGGGCCACAAGCUGCAGCCUCCCAAAGGUUACAAGGAGGAGGAGUUCAGCUGGAGCCAGUACCUGCGCAGCACAAGAGCUCAGGCUGCCCCCAAGCACCUGUUUGUGAGCCAGAGCCACAGUCCCCCACCCCUGGGCUUCCAGGUGGGCAUGAAGCUGGAGGCUGUUGACCGCAUGAACCCGUCCCUUGUCUGCGUGGCCAGUGUGACCGAUGUGGUGGACAGCCGCUUCCUGGUGCACUUUGACAACUGGGAUGAUACUUAUGACUACUGGUGUGAUCCCAGCAGCCCCUACAUCCACCCAGUGGGCUGGUGCCAGAAGCAAGGAAAGCCCCUCACCCCUCCACAAGACUACCCAGACCCUGAUAACUUCUGUUGGGAGAAAUAUCUGGAAGAAACUGGGGCCUCUGCUGUCCCCACCUGGGCCUUCAAGGUGCGACCCCCUCACAGCUUCCUGGUCAAUAUGAAGCUGGAGGCUGUGGACCGCAGGAACCCAGCCCUGAUUCGCGUGGCCAGCGUGGAGGAUGUGGAGGACCAUCGGAUAAAGAUCCACUUUGAUGGCUGGAGUCAUGGCUAUGAUUUCUGGAUCGACGCUGACCACCCAGACAUCCACCCUGCCGGCUGGUGCUCCAAGACAGGACAUCCCCUGCAGCCUCCUCUCGGACCCAGAGAGCCCAGCUCUGCCUCCCCUGGGGGCUGUCCCCCUCUCAGCUAUAGGAGCCUGCCCCACACUAGGACCUCCAAAUACAGCUUUCACCACCGGAAGUGCCCCACUCCUGGUUGCGACGGCUCUGGCCAUGUCACAGGCAAGUUCACAGCUCACCAUUGCCUCUCAGGCUGCCCACUGGCUGAGAGGAACCAGAGCCGGCUGAAAGCGGAGCUGUCUGACUCGGAGGCCUCAGCCCGCAAGAAGAACCUCUCAGGCUUCUCCCCAAGGAAGAAGCCUCGCCAUCACGGCCGAAUUGGACGCCCUCCGAAGUAUCGAAAGAUUCCGCAGGAAGAUUUCCAGACCCUCACGCCCGAUGUCGUGCACCAGUCCCUCUUCAUGUCAGCCCUGUCGGCCCACCCUGACCGCUCACUCUCAGUGUGCUGGGAGCAGCACUGCAAGCUCCUGCCAGGAGUAGCGGGCAUCUCAGCCUCGACAGUCGCCAAGUGGACCAUCGAUGAGAUGAUUGACGGCGAGGCCUUCCUUUUGCUGACACAGGCGGACAUUGUGAAGAUCAUGAGCGUCAAGCUGGGCCCAGCCUUGAAGAUCUAUAACGCCAUUCUCAUGUUCAAAAACGCUGAUGACACCUUAAAGUGACUGGCCCAGGGCUGGGCCCUCCUGCAGCCCCUGCUUGGCCUCCCUCUCCAGCUGAUGCUUUCUUCCUGACCUGAAUUCCUCAUACCCCACACGUCCCCAUGCUCCACCUAUAUCUGACCAGGCUGGUCCUUCUUAGAGGGUGCAUGGGAGCUGAGGAGCCCUGGGGAGGGUAGGCACCCAGCCCCAAGUCCUAGAGCUCAUUCGUCACCAGGCAUGUUGGUGAGGGCGUGACUGGCAGGGGCAUUACUCAUGGAGUCAGUUGGACUGUGGCAGCCCCCACAGCCCCAGUGGACUUUUAUUGUAUUACCAAAGGGUCUUUUUCUUGGCAGUGGAGGAGAGACUAGUAGAGCAGCAGUCCUUCAAUCUGAGGCCCCUUUCCCUUUUUUGGUAUCUCUGUGUACUUUUCUCUCCUUGGCUCCUUUCCUCCUGCCAAGAAGUGACCCCACCACAAAUGUAUUUACUCCUGGAGGUACCUCCUCUCUUUCUGUCUGCUGGUUUUGCUGCCCUCAUUCUGCUGCUUCGUUUCCUGGGCAGUGCCCCCAGCCAGACCCCACUGGCUCUUCCCCCUGAGAUAUGUGAACCUCGGAAACAUGUUUUCCUAAGAUCCCUUGGAAGUCUCUAGCUGCCUUUCUCUCUUUUGCCCAGAAUUGAGAGAUUUUGAGCCAAGAUGCCUUCCUGAACUUACCCAGUUCUGGACCAGUUGGCAUUUUAGUGUCCCACGCCAAGUCCAAGUUUCAGCAGAAUGAGCAGGUGGUUUGAGCCUGUUUUAUAGAUGGCAGAGGUUGAGGUUCCACUGCUGUUUUCCAUACACCCUUCAUGUGUUGAGUCUGGGAAGGAGUAAGCCUAGCCUGCCAGUAGCCUAGGUUAGGAGACCAGCAUAAGGAUUUGUUAGACAAUCUCGGGUCUUUGGCCAGAGGGGCAGCUCCAGCAGGCAUAGUGGUGCCUGAAGUUAGGAAUACUGUACUCUCUGUAGCUUUGGACCUCAGCCAAGGUAUUGCCCAUGGGGUGAUGGCUCCAGGCCUGCCAGGCCUUCUGCCAUGAGAAUGUAGCACUCUGUGUAGCACACACCCCCAUGACAUCAUUUAACCUGUCCCUUAAAUGUUGACCAUUAGCUCUUGCAGCGUCUUACAAAGACGACUUGAAGUUGGGAGUUAGGAAGGUGAACUUUUCUAUCUGAAUUCUCCGGGUCCCUGAAGCCCUCCUUGCCGCUCUCCAUCUGUCUUGCACUGCCAGCUGGGUCCCUGCUGGGGCUCUGGGACUUCCACUUCUCAGUCCACAUAGGAACCCAGCUUCCACUGAGUCACUGCCAAACCUGCCUCCCAGCCUGGGUGGGAAGGGGGAGAGCCACUGGUAGGAGCCAGCCCCACAUGGAGGUGAGGAGCCACUGCCAACCUCCCGUGUCCAGGUGCUGAUGUGGGCCUGCGGAGUGUGGGGCUGGUGCCUUCACCCAGACCCCUUCAAUCAUGUGAUGUGUGUGUGUGUGCAUGUGUGUGUGUGUGUGUGUGUGUGGCACUCUCAGAAGUGUUUGACAGGGUGCAGAUGUGAGGCUUAGUGUUGGGAAAAUGCCAAGGGCUAUUAUCAUUAAAAUUUGAAGCUUUAUUUUUCCCUUAGAAGUGGGAAACCCAGAGCUCUGUUGAUUUCCUACCACAACCCAGUAGGGGCCUCUCUCUGCCAUGGGCUGGACAGCUUUUUGAGGAAGCCAUUCAGCUCCCACAGUUGAGCUCCCACAGGGCUUUAGGUGUCCAUUCCCUCUCAACUGCUUAGAGGCAGCUUUGAGCACAGCCUUCCUGGAAGGAAGCUAGGCAAGACCUGCCACACAGCGAAGGUUGGGUUUACAAGGGUGACAUUGGUACCCCCUUGGCCAAGAGUAAAGAAGAACAAGUCUAAGCCUUGCUUUUAUCUUAGUUGUCUGGGUGGUAGCAGAACUCAUCAGCUCCUUAUCCUCAGUCUGUUCCUCUAUAAAAGAUGAGAGAUGUUCACUGACUUUGUGCAGUGAGAAGGCAGCAAGUACUCACGGCUGGUGCUGUGGGACCUCACAGCUUCUAAGGAGAGGGGCUGGGAGGGCCUUUGCCAUCAGAUCUGCCAAGCACCUAAUGCUUGCCUGUGGUGAAGGCAAGAUGGACCAAGGGCCUUGGAGAAAAGGGCUCCCAGGCUUCUGAACUUUGAGGCCUCAGCACUUUCUGCAUUAUCGUCAAACUCUUUGGAAAGAAACCAAAUCAUUAAAAAGUAGAAAGAAAUCUGCCUCUUGUCUGCCCUACUGCCCCUUUACCCCCACUCUGUCCCCAAAUGAUAUUAUUGCACCUUGACCUGGGAGCGCAGAGAGGGGAGGGAGUUGGCAGAGACUUCUGGUGCCCUCUGCCCUCCUAGCAACAGAUGCCACUUAUAUUUUGGCCCCUGGCAGCCUCGCCCAGCCCCUGAUCAGCCCAGGCCUAGGGCAGUUAGGACCUUUCUGUUUAUUUUCUGAAGCAGAGAGAAUGAUCUCAGAGUUUGCAAAUGAAGCCUUUUUUGCACUUUCAUUCACAUGCACUUUGGUGGGGUUACAUUUUUGUACUUGCCUCUUGUGUGUGCACAUGUGUGUAUGUGUUCUUUAAGAGAAUCUUCUGGCUUAAGCUAAGGUGACUCUUGAAGGAGAAAAAGUUACAAACAAAAUGUGGUGUGAUCUGUCAGUGUAUCAAAACAACAUAAAUAAACUUGAACAACUGAUACGCA